AGUGUGCUUUGAGUAGAAGCUGCACUGGGGCCGGGACUCGGAGGCGCGCUGCGUGAGCCGGCCGCAGAGCCAUGGCGGGCGGGGAAGACCGCGGGGACGGAGAGCCGGUAUCAGUGGUGACCGUGAGGGUGCAGUACCUGGAAGACACCGACCCCUUCGCAUGUGCCAACUUUCCGGAGCCGCGCCGGGCCCCCACCUGCAGCCUGGACGGGGCGCUGCCCUUGGGCGCGCAGAUACCCGCGGUGCACCGCCUGCUGGGAGCGCCGCUCAAGGUGAGGGAGGCCGGAGAAAGGUUGGGGCGAUCGGGGGUUCAGGGUGGGCGCCAUGAAAACUGGUGGGAGGUGCUCCGCGGGAAGAGGCUGGAGCGAGUGUUCUUCUCCGGAAAAGUCUUGGGCUGGGGUCCCAGGGUCCACUCUGCCCCGCCUGCGGGGGAGUCCCCUCUCAAGUUGAGGGGAAACUGAAGAGGGGUGCCAGGAACUUGGCUCCGCCAUUCUGACUGCCCUUCGAAUUAGGCGCACCUGGGGAGGUGCUCGAGUUCCACUCGCCGUCGGUCUGCCAGGGUGGCUUCCCUGGUCAGAGUGACGGUAGCCGCUUGGGCUGUAGCGGACCCUGGAGGCGGAGCUGGGGAGGGACCAGCUUCCACCUGCUUCAGGUGAGGUGGGGGCGGGACCACGAGGAGGGGCGGGCCCGAGGCGGACUACUAGAGGUGGCAGAGGUUUCCUGCGGUGUCAGGAAGCUGGAUUGGGGCUUGACCCUGUAGGUCAAUGGGAGUAUGGGAGUGCCGGCCGAGGAGAGACUUCACGGGGUGAGGGGAGUCCCCGCGAAGCGGUCUGGCCCGGGAUCCGCAGAGCGCAGGAGGCUGCACGGGUGUAAAAGCCCUUUGAGUCACCGCUCCCGCCCCCACCCCCGGACACUCGCCGCCCAUCGGCCCGCGCCUGAAAGUGAGAGGGAGGGCCGGACUAAUUUUAAACAGCCGGCCUGCCCUACUUUGCUGCCGCCCCGAAGCGGACUUGUGCACAGUGCGGAAAGAGGCCCUUUUCCAGAUGGCCAGCCUACCUCCUCUCCCCUCCCUCUCGCCGCCGUCAGCCCCCCGCAGGCAGCCCUUUCCGGCGCGCUGUUUCCGGGCCAGGACUCUGGGAGGCGCACUACCACCUCCACAAGCUCCCCACCAGCCCGGCCGCCUCCAGUGCUGGAGAAGAGGAGAGAGAGUCGGGGUGGGUGCCCUCCCCUGCUCCCAGCCUCAGCUGGGCGGCGAGUUGCGUAAACUUGCCCCUUGGGCCUGGGGUCUUCCCUGGAAUGUGCCCCGGGCCCCCAGCCCGCAUUCCUCGCGCUGCGGCCAGCCCCGCCUCUGAGCGCUGGCGGGAGGGGUGGUGAGACUAUUGGCCUGGAGAGUGGCACGUGUCCAGGCCAGAACCCCGGCUUCAAGGCCAUGGCUGGAAGGAUGCAGGACACUGCUCACCGCCAGUUUUGACUCAGCCCCCGCUUCUCUUGCCCUAUUCAGAGGGGCAAAUUGAGGUGUGCCUGGAAGAAGCGUGUGCAGCUGGAGGCCACCUCCCAUUCAGGAUGGGGGCUGGGAAGACAGGAGUGCUGAACUAAGACUGGUUCCCGCUUCCAGGCUCCUAAAGUCCGGAUCCUGAAAUAAGGACGGAUUCUGGCUCUGUCUCCCAGGCUGGAGUACAGUGGGGCUAUCUUGGCUCACUGCAACCUCCACCUCCCGGGUUCUAGCAAUUCUCGUGCCUCAGCCUUCCAAAUAGCUGGGAUUACAGGUGUGCGCCACCAUACUCAGUUGGAGGAUUGUGCUCUGCAAGUGUCUCCCUCCGGAUACUACCUGGACACCGAGCUGUCCCUGGAAGAGCAGCGGGAGAUGCUGGAGGGCUUCUAUGAAGAGAUCAGCAAAGGGCGGAAGCCCACGCUGAUCCUUCGGACCCAGCUCUCUGUGAGGGUCAACGCUAUCUUGGAAAAGCUGUAUAGCUCCAGUGGUCCUGAGCUCCGCCGCUCCCUCUUCUCACUGAAGCAGAUCUUCCAGGAGGACAAAGACCUGGUGCCUGAAUUUGUGCAUUCAGAGGGGCUGAGCUGCCUGAUCCGUGUGGGUGCUGCUGCCGACCACAACUACCAGAGCUACAUCCUUAGAGCGCUCGGCCAGCUGAUGCUCUUUGUGGAUGGAAUGCUGGGGGUGGUGGCCCACAGUGACACUAUUCAGUGGCUGUACACAUUGUGUGCCAGCCUGUCCCGCUUGGUGGUGAAGACAGCCCUGAAGCUGCUGUUGGUGUUUGUAGAAUACUCCGAAAACAACGCACCGCUGUUCAUCCGUGCAGUGAACUCUGUGGCCAGCACCACCGGUGCUCCUCCCUGGGCCAAUCUGGUGUCCAUCCUGGAGGAGAAGAAUGGCGCUGACCCUGAGUUGUUGGUGUACACGGUCACCCUCAUCAACAAGACGCUGGCGGCGCUCCCGGACCAGGACUCCUUCUACGAUGUGACGGAUGCACUGGAGCAGCAGGGCAUGGAAGCGCUGGUCCAGCGCCACCUGGGCACUGCGGGCACUGACGUCGACCUGCGCACGCAGCUUGUGCUCUACGAGAACGCCCUGAAAUUGGAGGAUGGAGACAUCGAAGAAGCCCCAGGCGCUGGUGGGCGGCGGGAACGACGAAAGCCUUCUUCUGAGGAGGGCAAGAGGAGCCGCCGUUCUCUGGAAGGCGGGGGCUGCCCCGCGCGUGCCCCGGAACCUGGCCCCACAGGCCCCGCCUCACCGGUAGGCCCCACCUCUUCCACCGGCCCCGCCCUGCUGACAGGCCCCGCCUCCAGCCCUGUGGGCCCUCCCUCCGGUCUCCAAGCUUCAGUGAACCUUUUUCCUACCAUCUCUGUGGCACCCUCAGCUGACACCUCCAGCGAGAGGAGCAUCUACAAAGCCCGGUUCCUGGAGAAUGUGGCGGCAGCAGAAACAGAGAAGCAGGUUGCGCUGGCCCAGGGCCGGGCAGAGACACUUGCCGGGGCCAUGCCCAAUGAGGCGGGUGGACACCCAGAUGCCCGGCAACUCUGGGACUCCCCAGAGACAGCCCCUGCAGCCAGAACACCCCAGAGCCCUGCCCCCUGUGUCCUGCUCCGGGCCCAGCGAAGCCUUGCACCAGAGCCCAAGGAGCCACUGAUACCAGCAAGCCCCAAGGCUGAGCCCAUCUGGGAGCUCCCUACCCGUGCACCCAGGCUCUCUAUUGGGGACCUGGACUUUUCAGAUCUAGGGGAGGAUGAAGACCAGGACAUGCUGAAUGUAGAGUCUGUGGAGGCUGGGAAAGACAUCCCAGCUCCCUCACCCCCACUGCCCCUGCUCUCGGGAGUACCCCCCCCUCCCCCACUUCCACCUCCCCCACCCAUCAAAGGCCCCUUCCCACCACCUCCACCUCUACCUCUGGCUGCCCCUCUUCCCCAUUCAGUGCCUGACAGCUCAGCCCUCCCCACUAAGAGGAAGACAGUAAAACUUUUCUGGCGUGAGCUGAAGCUGGCUGGGGGCCAUGGAGUCUCUGCAAGCCGCUUUGGGCCCUGCGCCACCCUCUGGGCUUCACUGGACCCUGUCUCAGUGGACACGGCCCGACUGGAACACCUCUUUGAGUCUCGUGCCAAAGAGGUGCUGCCCUCCAAGAAAGCUGGAGAGGGCCGCCGGACAAUGACCACAGUGCUGGACCCCAAGCGCAGCAACGCCAUCAACAUCGGCCUAACCACACUGCCACCUGUGCAUGUCAUUAAGGCUGCUCUGCUCAACUUUGAUGAGUUUGCUGUCAGCAAGGAUGGCAUUGAGAAGCUACUGACCAUGAUGCCCACGGAGGAAGAGCGGCAGAAGAUUGAGGAAGCCCAGCUGGCCAACCCUGACAUACCCCUGGGCCCAGCCGAGAACUUCCUGAUGACUCUUGCCUCCAUUGGCGGCCUCGCUGCUCGUCUACAACUCUGGGCCUUCAAGCUGGACUAUGACAGCAUGGAGCGGGAAAUUGCUGAGCCACUGUUUGACCUGAAAGUGGGUAUGGAACAGCUGGUACAGAAUGCCACCUUCCGCUGCAUCCUGGCUACCCUCCUAGCGGUGGGCAACUUCCUCAAUGGCUCCCAGGUGGACUUUGAACAGCUGACUGAGAACCUGGGGCAGCUGGAGCGCCGGAGCCGGGCAGCCGAGGAGAGCCUGCGGAGCUUGGCCAAGCAUGAGCUGGCCCCAGCCCUGCGUGCCCGCCUCACCCACUUCCUGGACCAGUGUGCCCGCCGUGUUGCCAUGCUAAGGAUAGUGCACCGCCGUGUCUGCAAUAGGUUCCAUGCCUUCCUGCUCUACCUGGGCUACACCCCGCAGGCGGCCCGUGAAGUGCGCAUCAUGCAGUUCUGCCACACGCUGCGGGAAUUUGCGCUUGAGUAUCGGACUUGCCGGGAACGAGUGCUACAGCAGCAGCAGAAGCAGGCCACAUACCGUGAGCGCAACAAGACCCGGGGACGCAUGAUCACCGAGACAGAGAAGUUCUCAGGUGUGGCUGGGGAAGCCCCCAGCAACCCCUCUGUCCCAGUAGCAGUGAGCAGCGGGCCAGGCCGGGGAGAUGCUGACAGUCAUGCUAGUAUGAAGAGUCUGCUGACCAGCAGGCCUGAGGACACCACACACAAUCGCCGCAGCAGAGGCAUGGUCCAGAGCAGCUCCCCAAUCAUGCCCACAGUGGGGCCCUCCACUGCAUCCCCAGAAGAACCCCCAGGCUCCAGUUUACCCAGUGAUACAUCAGAUGAGAUCAUGGACCUUCUGGUGCAGUCAGUGACCAAGAGCAGUCCUCGUGCCUUAGCUGCUAGGGAACGCAAGCGUUCCCGCGGCAACCGCAAGUCUUUGAGAAGGACGUUGAAGAGUGGGCUCGGAGAUGACCUGGUGCAGGCACUGGGACUAAGCAAGGGUCCUGGCCUGGAGGUGUGAAGGUGCUGUAUCCCGGAAAUCUAUCUGGACCCUGGACUGCAGUGCAGGAGAUGACAGAGUGAGGAGGGCCCAGAGCAGAAUUCUGGCCCCAGAACUCUGUGCCCAGGAGCCAUGCCUUGAGCAGUAUUAGCCGUGUGUGUAUGCAUGUGAGUGUGUGUGUAUGUGUGUGUGUGCAUGCAUAUGCAUGUGCAUGUGUGUGAGCUCCUUGAACGCACGGAGCAAAAUAAAAUUUUCUUAGCUAAUCCAA